ACUUUGUGGGAAAGGUGCCAGGUGCCAGCACUUCCAAGGGCACUGGAGCUGCCUUCUGCUGGAUUGGCUGCCCCAGCCAUCUUCUGAAAGGGAAUGAGCAGUGCCAUAGAGGCCCAGGGCGGUCAUGACAGAGCCCUGAACUACGUACCCUUAGGCAAGUAACUCAUUUUCUUUGUGUUGCAUUUUUUUUUCUUUUGUUCUGUUUUCAGCUUAUAAAUAGAAAGGCUGUCGUAAAUCAAUGUGUGGUUUUUUUUUGUUAUUUUUAUUUUCCUGGUGGAAUUUUAAAAAAUGAAAUCUUAUGCCAAUAUCUACUAUAAAAGUUAGAUGAAAACAGACUGCUCUAAGUGGGAGCUGGGGUGAGGACCCAGAACACUGUCCUUCUGACCCCUUCCUCUUACCCCUGCAGUGGCUCCCGAGCAGCUUGGGGCAUGGAAGAGCCCAGUUUAAGAAUCCUUUAAGGUUCUUUAAGGUUCCUUCCAGAUACAAAGCCCAGGGAUUCUCUGACUUAGGAGGGAAUUGAGGUAGGUCAGGGUGGGAAAGACACACAGCCUUAAAAGUUGAGAAGUGGGCUGUUUGAGAAGUGGGUUGCUUGAGAAGCGGAUUGUCUGAGAAGUGGGUUGCUUGGGGCUAAUCUAUAAAGUCUCCAUCUGUAAAGUUAUCCUAAAAUUAUGUCUUGUCUCUUAGGAAGGAUGUGCAGUGGUUAACUUUCCUAGGUCAGGACCUUUUACAAGAUGCUCUUCGGAAAUACCUACAUUUUUGAAUUUUACUAGAACGGGCUGGUCUGGGACUUGGAAGUACAUUGUGUAUAUGAAAGAAGAUAUUUGUUAUAGUACAAAAUGCAGAAUAGGUAACCUAGAAUGACAGUAGCCUCUUGGUAGGCUAGUAGUAUAUAGUUUUUAAAAGUAGUUUUUCAUGUGUUUGGGAUCAAAAGUCUCUUUGAGAAUCUGGUAACGUUUAUUGCACAAUUUUAGAAUACUCAUAACAUUGAUGAAGCUUAACUUUGGGCCUGCUAGGGAUUCAUGAAUUCCAGGUCUAAAGGGAAAAUCAUUUUUUCCUAAACACUAGAGAAUAUAGGAGAUCACUUAAAAUAUGUUUUAGGGAUUAAUAGGCAAAUGUAUUAGUUCUGAAGUCAUCAGAUGGCAGUUUCCAUGCCCAUGGUUUUUUUCUGCCCUAGAUGGCUCUGGAAACAAAGGUCAGUGGUCAGUGACAGGUGAAAGUCAAACACUGGCAUUUCCUGGAAGGACAGACUCUAGGGACACAGUCCAGUCCUCCCUCUAGCUCCUGACUCACUCAAGAAUAACAUUUAAAUAAUCCUACAACCCAAACAUUUGACAUCUGGGAAAACAAGGGAAGCUUGUUUCCCUGGGGAGAAUAUGGGAGGCUGACUCUGCUUUCCCCCAUGUGACAUCUAUUGUUUGGAGACCUGGCAGGUUCGGACUUGGCUGGGUAUCCCCUCUGUGGGGUAUGUGAUGGAACCAAGGGCGCUGGUGACAAGUGAAGGGAGAAGAGAGGCACCAGCAAGCCCCAGUCCUUACUGAAAGCCCUAAGCCUGGGUGGCCCAUGCAUCCUGUGCAGCCGUCUUGGCUCUCUCCUCGCGGCUGGUGUUAGUCACUCCUGGCGGUUUUACCGAUCCUUGAACAUCCGGAUUGCUCUCGUGGGCUUGGAAGUGUGGACCCACGGGAACAUGUGUGAAGUUUCAGAGAAUCCAUAUUCUACCCUCUGGUCCUUUCUCAGUUGGAGGCGCAAGCUGCUUGCCCAGAAGUACCAUGACAACGCCCAAUUAAUCACGGGCAUGUCCUUCCACGGCACCACCAUCGGCCUGGCCCCCCUCAUGGCCAUGUGCUCUGUGUACCAGUCUGGAGGAGUCAACAUGGACCACUCCGAGAAUGCCAUUGGCGUGGCUGCCACCAUGGCCCACGAGAUGGGCCACAACUUUGGCAUGACCCAUGAUUCUGCAGAUUGCUGCUCGGCCAGUGCGGCUGAUGGUGGGUGCAUCAUGGCAGCUGCCACUGGGCACCCCUUUCCCAAAGUGUUCAAUGGAUGCAACAGGAGGGAGCUGGACAGGUAUCUGCAGUCAGGUGGUGGAAUGUGUCUCUCCAACAUGCCAGACACCAGGAUGUUGUAUGGAGGCCGGAGGUGUGGGAACGGGUAUCUGGAAGAUGGGGAAGAGUGUGACUGUGGAGAAGAAGAGGAAUGUAACAACCCCUGCUGCAAUGCCUCUAAUUGUACCCUGAGGCCGGGGGCGGAGUGUGCUCACGGCUCCUGCUGCCACCAGUGUAAGCUGUUGGCUCCUGGGACCCUGUGCCGCGAGCAGGCCAGGCAGUGUGACCUCCCGGAGUUCUGUACGGGCAAGUCUCCCCACUGCCCUACCAACUUCUACCAGAUGGAUGGUACCCCCUGUGAGGGCGGCCAGGCCUACUGCUACAACGGCAUGUGCCUCACCUACCAGGAGCAGUGCCAGCAGCUGUGGGGACCCGGAGCCCGACCUGCCCCUGACCUCUGCUUCGAGAAGGUGAAUGUGGCAGGAGACACCUUUGGAAACUGUGGAAAGGACAUGAAUGGUGAACACAGGAAGUGCAACAUGAGAGAUGCGAAGUGUGGGAAGAUCCAGUGUCAGAGCUCUGAGGCCCGGCCCCUGGAGUCCAACGCGGUGCCCAUUGACACCACUAUCAUCAUGAAUGGGAGGCAGAUCCAGUGCCGGGGCACCCACGUCUACCGAGGUCCUGAGGAGGAGGGUGACAUGCUGGACCCAGGGCUGGUGAUGACUGGAACCAAGUGUGGCUACAACCAUAUUUGCUUUGAGGGGCAGUGCAGGAACACCUCCUUCUUUGAAACUGAAGGCUGUGGGAAGAAGUGCAAUGGCCAUGGGGUCUGUAACAACAACCAGAACUGCCACUGCCUGCCGGGCUGGGCCCCGCCCUUCUGCAACACACCGGGCCACGGGGGCAGUAUCGACAGUGGGCCUAUGCCCCCUGAGAGUGUGGGUCCUGUGGUAGCUGGAGUGUUGGUGGCCAUCUUGGUGCUGGCGGUCCUCAUGCUGAUGUACUACUGCUGCAGACAGAACAACAAACUAGGCCAACUCAAGCCCUCAGCUCUCCCUUCCAAGCUGAGGCAACAGUUCAGUUGUCCCUUCAGGGUUUCUCAGAACAGCGGGACUGGUCAUGCCAACCCAACUUUCAAGCUGCAGACGCCCCAGGGCAAGCGAAAGGUGAUCAACACUCCGGAAAUCCUGCGGAAGCCCUCCCAGCCUCCUCCCCGGCCCCCUCCAGAUUAUCUGCGUGGUGGGUCCCCACCUGCACCACUGCCAGCUCACCUGAGCAGGGCUGCUAGGAACUCCCCAGGGCCCGGGUCUCAAAUAGAGAGGACGGAGUCGUCCAGGAGGCCUCCUCCAAGCCGGCCAAUUCCCCCCGCACCAAAUUGCAUCGUUUCCCAGGACUUCUCCAGGCCUCGGCCGCCCCAGAAGGCACUCCCGGCAAACCCAGUGCCAGGCCGCAGGAGCCUCCCCAGGCCAGGAGGUGCAUCCCCACUGCGGCCCCCUGGUGCUGGCCCUCAGCAGUCCCGGCCUCUGGCAGCACUUGCCCCAAAGUUUCCAGAAUACAGAUCACAGAGGGCUGGAGGGAUGAUUAGCUCGAAAAUCUAGACCUGUCCAAGGGGCUUCUCCCUUUCCUUGAGCUCUCUGGACACUGCAGAGGACCCAUGGCCAUGGAACCCUGAAGAAGCAUGUCUGGCCGCCUCUGAGCUCCUCCCACCCUCCUCCAGGAACCUCCACAUCUCCAAAAAUCUCCCUGUUGACUCAGUGCCUCCUCGGCUUCCUUGGAAGCCCAGAGGGACUAUGAUCUGAUGGCCUCUAGGUGUUGUUUUGUGCAAUAUACAGCCCCAGGUAGGGAGGGGAGAGUAUGAGGAGGGUGACUGGCAGCUUCUCCUCCAGACUCCUAGCCCCGAGGUGCUGAUGGAGAUGCUCAAGGCCAGCAAGCCCCUCAGGCCAGCACUUCGCUUGCAGAAGCCAUCCAUUCACUCCUGGGGUGCAGGGCACGCAAGAGAGCUUCCCAUUGCUUCUGCUCUCCUCAGAGGUCCCGGGCUGGAUGGAGGCUGGUACUUACCCACCCCUUUUAGCUUUUAGGGAUUAAGGAAGGGUCAAGCCAGCCACUGCUGUGGCCCUGCCCAGGGCUUGGUUGAGGGAACGGCUUCUGGCUGUAUGGCUGCAUGUGACAAGCCACGUCCCCUCCCACCUCUCCCCAAACCCCUGCAUCCCUGUAUUCACACGGGUCACUCUGACUCAGACAGGUACUAUUCGUAGGCAGUGUAGACAGCAGGAGGAGCACCGGGCUUGGGCUUCCUCUGAGCCGUGAUGCCAAAGGUUGCGACUCCUGACUCUGGAUAAUUUUUAGUUGCUCUUUGUUUUCUCUGCCGCACUUUCCUGGUGCCCCACGCUUUUCUCUCUUCCUUCCCCUCUCAUUCUCCCUCUAAUGUGUGGUGCUUUGGUGAGCAAACCCUCAGCAGUCCUGACCUUCGGGUGACCAGGUGCUUGUGACCUACAAGUCAGAGUCCUCUCUCACAGUCGGCCACUGGAUUUCCCUCACUGGCUCUCAGGAGUGUGACCAGAGUAGACUUGGGGCAUGGCCAUUGGGGUCAUAUGUUUAUUUUUCAUUGUGUUUUGUGACCUCAGCAGGGUGGGGGUCUUCCUCCUUACUCUAAGCUAAAUCUAGGUGAGGUUUCCCCUUAGGGAGCCCAGCUAUUUACAAAGUACACACGAGGGAGCAGGCUGGUCAUUGACUUCGGGCUGGACCGUUGCCCUCUGAGCAGAGAACAGACCCAUUUCUGGGAGCUGCCCGAGAUCACUGGAGAAGGCAGCCAGCAGCAGCUGCACUGGAACAGUCAGAGCAGGGAGCCUCUUCCUCAACCCAGCUUUUUGUCAUUCACUUCCUUUUGUUCUCUCUCUGGUCACUGCCCUUACCUGACCCUCACAGAAAGAGAGCUCUGAGCAGGUGAGGGGGUCUGCGGUGGCUCCUGUCUUCCCUGCAGCAGGGAAGGAGGGCCGUGUGGUGCUUUGCUAGAUAGGACGGUUUUUGCAAAGCACCUGGAGAUGUUUGCUGGGAGAUAGACUCCCACUCCACAAAGGUGCUGGGUGGCUCUCCGGACAGGAGCUGGCCUGACUCUCACUCCUCUGAGGCUUUCCUGGGGCCUCCUCCCAUCCUGCCAUGAGCAAUUGUUUGCUCUUGAAAACCUCACUGCAAGGCUGAGGCUGAGCUUCUGAUUCACCACCCCAGGGCCUCCUUAUAGUUCUCUGCACACAAUAGGUGCUUCUUGGAUGUUCUUGGGUUUGGAAAUAAGUGGAAAAUACGGGAUGUACCCCUGGGGGAAAAGCCUGGGUUGGGUUUAGAAAGAUCUCAGGAAAAUGAGUUUCUCUUCCCUCAGGGUGGCUGUGAUACAGGUUCCCCAUGUCCUUGCCGUGGGUCAUCCUUGCUGUGGGUCAUCCUUGCUGUGGAGAUCCAUUCCCCACCUUUCCUGUGGCCCAACCUUUUAUUUAAAUGUGCUACCCUCUGCCUCAAGGCUUGGUUCCUGGAAAGUAAAGGUGAAAACAUCCCCUUUCACCCCUCUGCAAAACAAACAAGCAACAUCCUCAAAACCCAACCCCAUGCCUCACAGAGCUUCCUGUGGCUUCUCCAGCCUUUCUCCCUCACAUCAGGAGGUAGAUAGCUCUGAAAUGACAGCGCCACAGCCAUAGUGACUGCAUGAGCCAUCUGAACCUGCAGUCCACCCUCCCUGGAACCACACCAGAAAGAGACCUGGGUUGUCGUUUUCUUGCUUUUUGUUUUGUUUUGUUUUAUUAUUUUCAUAUCACCUCCAUCCCAUAAAGUUGUACUGUGAACUGGAAGAUGGUGGAAUGUUUUGGAAUUUGAUAGACUUUCGGCAACCAGUUCUACUAAUGCUUCACUCCUGGCUCUGUUCAGGGAGGCUGCCCAGGAGGAAGACUGGCCAUUAUGCAUCCCCUUUUCUUUCCAGUGCCCAGUAUGCUGUUUUGAGGUGUCAAAUACAAAUAAAUCUGGGCUUAGGGAAGGAGAGACCUUAUUCCAAAGCACGAUUGCAGAAGGGGAAAGGGAAUAUUGCAAAAGGGAGAGGAAGGGGCCUUAUGGGAAUAGUGAAAAGGCUCAGACCGACCGAUGGCAAGAUCUGCAAGCGUCUCAAAGCCCAGGCAGAAAAGGACUUUUCUUUUAUUGGAAGAAGUAAACAUGGCUAGAAAGAACCACGUUCAGGGAAUGACGUUGUGCCCAGCCUUUUUUUUUUUUUUUUUUUUUUUGUCUCCAGGGGAGGGGCUGUUUGCUGGCUCAGGCUGAGGAUGGCCCAAAGUCCAGGGUCUGGUGGGGAGGAGGGAAGCUUAACUCAAGUUUGGGUUAGUGAGUUAGCAAGCUCUUUGUGCAGAUGGGGAUGUAGGUAAAUCUUUUUAAAAGUGAAAUUAACCUCCUGCCAAUUUUACAACCCAAGAAUUUUUUUUUAAGGGCCUUGGAGCCAUCUCUAAAACAAACCUCAAGGGAUUUAGUGCCCUGUCUCCCUGUCUCUAGAAGCCUUAGCCUGGGCACCUGGCUCAAUCUUGUAACUGCCUGCUAGCCAUAGAUUCCUUUCAGCCUUGCUGACUUCUCCCUAUAAAAGUAAAGCCUUUUUCUGCCCCAGCUCUGAGACACUUGCAGAUCUUAAGGUCUGAGACUUGCUGAUUUUCUGGUUGGAGUGUUUUUUUGUAUUGCCAUAGUCCCUUCCCCCUGAAGCAAUAGCCCCUCCCCACCUCCUGCAAUACGCCUUUCCAAUCUUUAUUGGAAGUCUCUCCCUGCCUACUUCCUAAUUUAUUCUUAUUUGACAGAGGGUAUGGAAGACUUGCAAUUUGAAAACUGGGGACCAGUUCCAAAGUCAGUAAUUGUGUUAACCACGUGUAUAACAGCUCUGCUGGACACCCAAGAAAGCCAUGGGAACGCCAACUGGAAAGGUCCCCUUCCCCAGGGGAGCCUGCGAAGGAGAGGUUCUGUAGAAUCCAAGCCCACAUUUCCAAAGUCACCCCCAACGCGUCCUCUCACACCGUCCACUGUGCGUUUGUAUGUGUCUGGGAUCCAGGGCAAUGUGAAUUUUCUUUUUAUUUGGGAGAUUGUUCACGGAAAACAGAUCUUCUUCUCUCUUGUCCACCUAUUAAUUGUUUACAAUAUUUGUACAUCUAUGCAAAAUACUUGAAUGGGCCAUGGUGCCUUUUUUCCUUGUUAGUAUUUAAUUAAAAAUGAAUUGUUUGUCAUUUGCAAUGUUA